AUUAGUACACACUUGUUGAUUAAUGGAAAUGUUUACAGAUCCCCAAGCCUGGCAAGGGAAUUUCUUCAACUCCCUGCCCCCCAGCCCUCCUUAUCAAAGGACACCAUUUUGGCAAGCUCUAUCACCAAGGAGCCAAACAUCCUACAAGACACAGUGACCAUACUAAUUAUACCCCCUGCAAAGCCCAGCUUGAAACCUUCACUUAGGAACGUAAUCGUGUCCCCUAUCCUACUUCCCCUUCCUAAUUCCACAGCUGCUCAAUAAAGUACAAGAGCUUAACAGUGUGUUGGCGCUUUGCUUUGGUCUAUCUUUGAGCGCCCACUAGACCCACUGGACUCACCUCCCCCAUCUCUUCUGGGUUCCUUCCUCUGAGCCUUGGGACCCCUGAGCUUGCAGAGAUGAGGCCGCCAUGUCCUCUGCCUAGCCGCAGAGAGCCCCAGUGGGAGGCCAGCGUCCUCAGAUUCACCUGCCUUGGACUUAACCCAAGCAUGGCUGAUGGCCUUCCAAAUAUUAAAGUCAUUGCCAUCCAGAUUUCUAAAUUAAAUUCCCUGUUGAAAGAAACGUUUUCUGUUUCCUGAAGGCUAGCAGGCCCUGGGAAAGAAGGCUUUUCAUCCCAACACUCCCUCUCUUCUGAUCCACAGGAAGGUGGUGGGAGCUCAUCACAGGACCAGGUUAGAAAGCCCUGAACCCUGGACCCUCAGGGCCAGCAGGAAAUGCAGAUGUCAUCUCAUGCACCCUUCCUGCCUCUCGGGACUGGAGUCCCUGCAGAGUGCUUGAGAGAUGGCCCUCCAGCCUCCCAGUGAGGGGCAGCCGAUUACCUUGGAAGCAACCCAUUCCGUGGCUGGGCUGAAAUCUGUCAAUAGUCCUAGUGCUGGGCUUAGCCCUUUGUUCUGUUCACCCCUCCCCUAACACUCAUCCCUCCACCCAUUCAGAGAUCAAAGUACCUCUGCUCAAGCUGGCCUGAGAUAGGAGGUCGGGAGGAUGUGAUGGGGUGACUCAGAAGAAUAGACAGAUUUUCAGCCUUUAUGAGGUGGAGACGCUCUCAUCAGGCUUCUGUUGAAUUCCCAGGGCCCCAGGAAUGCCUUUAUCCAAAAAGGCUCCAGAUACUCACCCCAGAACUAAAGAGAAUUGAUUUGUGGAUUCUCUGAUGUUUGGAUUAUCUGUGACUUAGGAUAAUCACAAAUUGGCCUGAUGGUUUGUGACGCCGGUUUGAAGUGGAGGGAAGGAGGAAAUAUCUGAAAUCUGAACCAGCUGGAGCUGGGCAGAUGCUACUGAUCCCAAGGUCACAGCCCUGCUGAAGGCGAAGAAAACAAGGACUCGGCAAGGCGUGGAGUGGGGUGUGGGGAGGGGGUACCCGGCAUUUCACCUCUGGCUGGUGGGGCCAAGUAUUCCCUAAUCCCUGCCACUGCCCACCCCACCACACAGGCAUCUUUGAAACCCCAGGGCUGCAAGCCCUUGUGGGCAGCCAACUGCCCUCCCCUGGGGCCACCCUUCCCCCAGCCGGGGACAGGCUCUCCAGGGCUGACUCAGUGUCCUGUGGGGUUAGUCACAUUCACUUAUAGCUGCAGAGUCAGAGGCCAAGGAUGGAGAUCCAGUCUCCAGGACCCACUCCCUGCCUGGCAAGACGUGGAGUCACCUAGCAGAGGGCGAGGGCAUCCAGGGAGGGCCAGAUCCAGAGGCUCCCAGGCCCUGCACUGCCACUCCCCAGCAGAGACAGCAGGGUUGAGAGGCAGCCACACCCUGGUGUCCCCAGUCCUCAGGAAAGGGAAGAGCAUGCAUGCUGCUGAGGGCCCUGAAUAAAUCACUUUUACUUAUUUUUAAAUUGUGAGCACAUCUUACGUGCUAAAGAGUGCAUAAAUGUAUUUGUUUAAUUUGAAGAAUAACUAUGUAGUAAGAACCUGUGUAACCACCACCCAGGUCAGGAAAGGAAACCUCAUUAGCACCCCUGCAGCCCUCACGAUCACAGAUAUCCCUGUUCCUCCACCUAGAGGCAAUCGCCAUCCUAACUUUUGUACUGGCCUCAUCUUCCUUUCUGGCCUUACCGCCUACGGAUGUACCUUGAAGAAGGGAGCCUGGUGUUGACUGCAUUUGGAUUUAAUGUAGAUGAGACAGAUGAGACGCAACAUUUCUGUGUGCCUUGCUCUUCUGCUCAUCACUGGGUCUCCAGUCCAGCAAUGAUGGAAAAAAACACCUCCGAGGGCCCUGCCUGCAGUCCAGAGGAGACCGCAUCUGAAUCUGCCAAGGUGCCCACAGCAGAGCCUCCCGGAGAAGUGGCAGUAUCAGAGUCCACCAGAGAAGAGCAGGUGCCCAAGCCGCAGGCCCCUGCCCCACAGGCCCCUACAGCCUCCACAGCCACUAAGCCUGCACCCCCAAGUGAAGAUGUCCCCAGUGCCCCACUGCUGCUGACCCUGGAUGAUGUGAGCAGCAGCUCUGUGACUGUGAGCUGGGAGCCCCCAGAGAGGCUGGGGAGGCUGGGCCUCCAGGGCUAUGUGCUGGAGCUCUGCAGAGAGGGAGCCUCGGAGUGGGUGCCUGUGAGUGCCCGGCCCAUGAUGGUGACCCAGCAGACUGUGCGGAACCUGGCUCUGGGAGACAAGUUCCUCCUGCGCGUGUCUGCAGUGAGUUCUGCAGGGGCUGGCCCGCCGGCCAUGCUGGACCAGCCCAUCCACAUCCGAGAGAACAUUGAGGCCCCCAAGAUCCGUGUCCCCCGCCACCUCCGUCAGACCUACAUCCGCCAGGUGGGAGAGACGGUCAACCUGCAAAUCCCCUUCCAGGGGAAGCCUAAGCCUCAGGCCACAUGGACCCACAACGGCCAUGCCCUGGACAGCCAGCGGGUGAGCAUGCGCACCGGGGACCAGGACUCCAUCCUCUUCAUUCGCUCGGCCCAGCGCUCCGACUCUGGCCGCUACGAGCUCACUGUGCGCGUGGAAGACCUGGAGGCCAAGGCAGUCAUUGACAUCCUGGUGAUUGAGAAACCUGGACCCCCCAGCAGCAUCAGGCUCCUGGACGUCUGGGGCUGCAAUGCUGCUCUUCAGUGGACGCCACCCCAGGACACAGGCAACACAGAGCUCCUGGGCUACAUGGUGCAGAAGGCAGACAAAAAGACAGGGCAAUGGUUCACAGUGCUGGAGCGCUACCACCCAACCACCUGCACCAUCUCUGACCUCAUCAUCGGCAACUCGUACUCCUUCCGGGUCUUCUCAGAAAACCUGUGUGGACUCAGCACCUCGGCCACCGUCACCAAGGAGCUCGCCCACAUCCAGAAGGCAGAUAUUGCUGCCAAACCUAAAGGGUUUAUUGAGCGAGACUUCUCAGAAGCCCCCUCAUUCACCCAGCCCCUGGCUGACCACACCUCCACCCCUGGCUACAGCACCCAGUUGUUCUGCAGUGUCCGAGCUUCACCCAAGCCCAAGAUCAUCUGGAUGAAAAACAAGAUGGAGAUCCAGGGCAACCCCAAAUACCGCGCCCUCUCUGAGCAAGGCGUCUGCACCCUAGAGAUCCGGAAACCCAGCCCCUUUGAUUCUGGGGUCUACACCUGCAAGGCCAUAAAUGUGCUGGGGGAGGCAUCUGUGGACUGCCGGCUGGAGGUCAAAGCCUCAGCCGCACACUGAAGUCACGGGAGGAGGCUGUGAUGAGGAGCCAGGUGCUGCAGGCCUGAGGGGCCAGGUCCACCAGGCCUACAGUCAAACUCCAGAGAUGCCCAAGACCCCCGCUUCCAUAGCGACGGCUGAUGGAACCGCCCCUGGUACCUGCUGGCCUCCCUUCCCCAGAGGCUGGUGUCCAGAACUCAGGAAUGGGCCUGGUAGGCCCCAGGCCAGACUAACUGGGCUCAAGGGGUGCUGGAAGGCGCAGAGAUUGGAGUGCCCUGCGGAGUUGCACUCUGGGUGGGAAGCACUCAAAUAAAGAUGCGUGGUGUUAACAGUG